AGUACAAACUCAGGACUCUCCCCCGCCCAGCCGCCCCUACACAAGGACUCGCCGAACACACCUUGAAUCCCGCGCCAGAGCGCAGCCCGGAACUGCAGCUCGCGGCGCGGGCCCAGGACUGAGCAGCUAGGCGCGAGCGAAAACAAACAGCUGGGGCUGCGAGCGCCCCCGCCCCGGCCCCGAGAGCACGCCGGCCCAGUCCCCCACCUGGGGCGCCCGUCUGCCCACCAUGAGGAAGAUCCGCGCCAAUGCCAUCGCCAUCCUGACCGUAGCCUGGAUCCUGGGCACUUUCUACUACUUAUGGCAGGACAACCGAGCCCACGCAGCAUCCUCCGGCGGCCGGGGCGCGCAGAGGGCAGGCAGGAGGUCGGAGCAGCUCCGCGAGGACCGCACCAUCCCGCUCAUUGUGACAGGAACUCCCUCGAAAGGCUUUGAUGAGAAGGCCUACCUGUCGGCCAAGCAGCUGAAGGCUGGAGAGGACCCCUACAGACAGCACGCCUUCAACCAGCUGGAGAGUGACAAGCUGAGCCCAGACCGGCCCAUCCGGGACACCCGCCAUUACAGCUGCCCAUCUGUGUCCUACUCCUCGGACCUGCCAGCCACCAGCGUCAUCAUCACCUUCCACAAUGAGGCCCGUUCCACCCUGCUGCGCACAGUGAAGAGUGUCCUGAACCGAACUCCUGCCAACUUGAUCCAGGAGAUCAUUUUAGUGGAUGACUUCAGCUCAGAUCCGGAAGACUGUCUACUCCUGACCAGGAUCCCCAAGGUCAAGUGCCUGCGCAAUGAUCGGCGGGAAGGGCUGAUCCGGUCCCGAGUGCGUGGGGCGGACGUGGCUGCAGCUACCGUUCUCACCUUUCUGGAUAGCCACUGCGAAGUGAACACCGAGUGGCUGCCGCCCAUGCUGCAGCGGGUGAAGGAGGACCACACCCGCGUGGUGAGUCCCAUCAUUGAUGUCAUCAGUCUGGAUAAUUUUGCCUACCUUGCAGCAUCUGCUGACCUUCGUGGAGGGUUCGACUGGAGCCUGCAUUUCAAGUGGGAGCAGAUCCCUCUUGAGCAGAAGAUGACCCGGACAGACCCCACCAGGCCCAUAAGGACGCCUGUCAUAGCUGGAGGAAUCUUCGUGAUCGACAAGUCCUGGUUUAACCACUUGGGAAAGUAUGAUGCCCAGAUGGACAUCUGGGGGGGAGAGAAUUUUGAGCUCUCCUUCAGGGUGUGGAUGUGUGGUGGCAGUCUGGAGAUCGUCCCCUGCAGCCGGGUGGGCCAUGUCUUCAGGAAACGGCACCCCUACAACUUCCCUGAGGGUAAUGCCCUCACCUACAUCAGGAAUACUAAGCGCACUGCAGAAGUGUGGAUGGAUGAAUACAAGCAAUACUACUAUGAGGCCCGGCCCUCGGCCAUCGGGAAGGCCUUCGGCAGUGUGGCUACGCGGAUAGAGCAGAGGAAGAAGAUGAACUGCAAGUCCUUCCGCUGGUACCUGGAGAACGUCUACCCAGAGCUCACGGUCCCCGUGAAGGAAGCACUCCCCGGCAUCAUUAAGCAGGGGGUGAACUGCUUAGAAUCUCAGGGCCAGAACACAGCUGGUGACUUCCUGCUUGGAAUGGGGAUCUGCAGAGGGUCUGCCAAGAACCCGCAGCCCGCCCAGGCAUGGCUGUUCAGUGACCACCUCAUCCAGCAGCAGGGGAAGUGCCUGGCUGCCACCUCCACCUUAAUGUCCUCCCCUGGAUCCCCAGUCAUACUGCAGAUGUGCAACCCUAGAGAAGGCAAGCAGAAAUGGAGGAGAAAAGGAUCUUUCAUCCAGCAUUCAGUCAGUGGCCUCUGCCUGGAGACAAAGCCUGCCCAGCUGGUGACCAGCAAGUGUCAGGCUGACGCCCAGGCCCAGCAGUGGCAGCUGUUGCCACACACAUGACGGAGGGAUUUUCUUGAAGGGUCAGCUAUUGCACUGUGCUGGGAGGCUGGCUGUGGCUCCUGUUUGUGAAGAGAACUCCCAGUUCCUUUUCACAGCCGCUGAGAACACAUCCACACAUCUACCCCACGGCCUUGUCUUGGAACUGCUCCUGCUAUCCCCACACCCUGCUUCCUCACCCCACUGGCUCUUGGGCAAAUGACUGUUGGUACCAGGACCCUGGGGGUCUCCCCUACAAAGCAGACCAGCCUGGGGCAGAUAUACCUACCACAGGAGCCCCCUGUCUUUCAUAGGCCAAGGAUCCACAUACCCAUAGAGUUCAUGGAUUCUAGAGGGUCUAGGAAUCUCUUGAAAUUGUCCCUAAAAUACUGCAUGUGUGUGCAUACAUGCAUUUUCCUGGGGAAAAAGUCCAUGGCUUCUAAAAGAGGUCCCUGAUCCCCAAAGGGCCUGAACCUCUGCUCUGGAUUGAAGCCACUGUCUGCCCAAGCUGCCACCCCCUAAUCUUCCUCCCUGGCGUGCUCAAACUGCCAUCGCCUGCUCCCUCCACACGGCCCUUGGGGUCAGCAGCCAAGUGUCUGUGGUCCGCAGCACCUGCUCUGGAGGGCUCUCCAGCAGUUUCGCCUCCUGACUCUCACCAGCGUCCUCUCGGCAGCACUCCCGUGCCCAAGUGCACCCCUCUGGACUUGCCAGCGCAGGCCCCUUCGCUCCCAGGGCCAUGCUUUGCCUGUCCUCUGUCGUGAUGUUUCUUCCGCAGCCAGGUGCAGCCUCAGAUCCCCUGUUCAUCUGGGAAGCCUCCUGCCACAGCUUAGGACAGAACUGGGCCCAGGGCAAAGGCCUCUCCCCAGAGGAUGGACUAGAAGGCCUGGGCCACACUCGGGCAUGGACCUUUGGGGCUGGGGAGCCGGGGCUGCGCCUGUUGAAUGUAAGAGGACUGCUGACCAGAGGGCCUUCAAGAGGGUCUCUCUGUCCUUUGCUGUGGUCAGAUCAGGCUCUGCACUUAUCAGCCGGUCCUUUGUGGCAACGCAGCCCUGUUCUGUUUUUGCUUUUCCUCUUCUUGACCAAAGCAUGUGCCACUAGCUGUCCUUGAGGACCUCGUCUUUAUGAAACACACACCUGGAAUAAAACCACUUCUUACAUGUCCACAUGCACCAGCGCCUUCCUUUCUGCCUCCAGGCCUAGCCCUUCAGCACACCCUCCCCCGCCUCGUGGGGAAAGUCCGGGCCUCCUUUCUGUAAAAGUGAAACUGAACAUGCUCAAGUCUAGCCCUGUCCUGCACCUGGUAGCUUGCUCGUCGGCCUCCAUGCCCUGUGGUGCCCCAGGAACUCCUGACUGCUCUGGUGGGGGCCAACAGGUGGCCCUACUGCAAGGGCAGGCCUUGGACCAAAACCAGGAAUCAGCACAGGUCAGGUGGAGCCCAGGCUCCUGUGGCCUCAUUAUGGGAUUCUACUUGGGGCUUAGAAAUGGAAAGCAAAUUGCUUCUCCAAAUAGGUAUUGCCCUGCCGCCGUGCUUGCCUUUAGCCAGCCCUCUCUCCUUCCCUGUGAGCCAGGCCUGUCCCCUCGGAGCUGCCCUCCCCUGCUCUACCACACAAGAAGGCAGUGGUACAAAUUCAGGCAGGACAUACUUCCUGGGUAAAAACAGCAAAAUAAUUCUGAAAAGAGUCUUACCAGACCAGCUUUGCUUGAUUGGGUAGCAGAUGCUCUGCCUAAUGUUCCCAUGGAAACCAAUGGAAAACCCCCACCAUGUCUGUGAUCAGAAGCUGAACCUACCCAGGUAAAAAUAAACGCUGCUUCAACAUACAUAUGAACUGCAGCUGGCAGGCCAGCACACCACUAGCCUCUCCUGGACGCAACCAUUUCUGCCCUCAGCCCCACUUUGCCGUGGGGCUGCUGAUCUGGAGUUACCCAGAACUUCUGACCCCUGGGCCUGAGGAGCCUGGAGCAAAGCCCUAGCUGGCUGCAGAGAAUACACCUUGGCUACAAUGUCCAGCUUGGUCUGGGCUUAGGAGCAAGUCACUGUAAAAGACCUUGGCUGCAGCCUCCAUUCCCCCAUCCACCCCUCCGUCCUCUCAGGGAGCACAGCCCACCACCCACCGCCUACUCAGGGCUCCCUCCUGGCGCGCUGAGCCCCAUUUCCACUCUCCAUCUAUUUUCACCCUCAGCCUUGGAGGGCUCUGGUGCUUGCUUCUCCUGAGUCAGGCUCUCUCCUCUUGCUUGCUCUCCUCCAAACCUACCUCUCCCAAAGCCCAUUUUCUGUGCCACCCAGUUUUUUCCCUAGGAGAUAAGGCUGUCAGCCUUUAGCCAGGCCCUGGAGGAAUCAGCAAAAGCCCCAGGCUGGGUAUUAACAGUUACGUCACUGGCAGGAGAGUCCCCCGAAAGCCUAUGGGCAGGGCAGCAGAAGGGACUUCUGCACCAGGGCCAGACUCCCAUUUGUACAGCAGGGAGCUGUUCCUGAGGAUCCCUGGGCCUCUGUGACUUGGCUUCAGUUUUUACAAGGGCUGUUCCCCCUGGCCCCUCAGGAAGGCUGUCUCCAUCUGCAGUUGGGAGAAAUAACCUGGACAAUAUGACUGUCGUCCCAGGGUUCCAGCACCCCAAGGCCUGCGGGGGAUGUCUCCCAGCACUGCAUGGGGUGUGGUCCUUCUCCCACCAGGGAACAGGAAAGGAAACCUGGAAGGGAAAGGCUGGCAUUUAUAACGUCUGUAAUUUCAUUGCCAACAAUGUUCUCAGUGUGUUUGGUAUUUGUGUGUCCCUGUGAUGGUCUGAGUCAGUGCUCCUCCAGAAGGAGGGGGCAACCCAGCCAGCUUCUCUAAUGGGAAGAGGUCUUCACUGCCAGGCACUUAGGAAAGACCUGGAGAUGGAUCAGGGGAGGGCCUACUCUCCUGGGCUUGCAGCUGGGCUGUCUGAGUAGCCGACCUGGACUGAGGCUCCAGAGCCAUCUGAGGACAAUUUCUCCUGCUUAAUUCAGCCCUGUGAAGCGUGGAGAAGAGUGUACUAGGGGUGCGGACUCUUGGGUCUUUAAGACCCAUUCAAGCCAGGCGCAGUGGCUCACACCUGUAAUCCCAAAUAUUCAGGAGGCUGAAUUGGGAGGGUCCUUUGAACCCAGGGGAGUUCGAGACCAGCCUGGGCAACAUAGCGAGACCCUAUCUCUAUAAAUAAAAAUUCAAAUCAACUUCAAAAAAUACCCAUUCAGCUGGAUCCCUCACUACUCUGCCAUUUGCCAGCUGUGAGCUCUUUUUUUUUUUUUUUUUUUGAGACAGAGUGUUGCUCUGUCACCCAGGCUGGAGAGCAGUGGCAUGAUCUCCACUUACUGCAAGCUCUGCCUCCUGGGUUCACGCCAUUCUCCUGCCUCAGCCUCCCGAGUAGCUGGGACUACAGGCGCCCACCACCAUGCCCAGCUAAUUUUUUUUGUAUUUUUAGUAGAGACAGGGUUUCACCGUGUUACCCAGGAUGGUCUCCAUCUCCUGACCUCGUGAUCCACCCGCCUCGGCCUCCCAAAGUGCUGGGAUUACAGGCGUGAGCCACUGCGCCUGACUGAGCUCUUGAAUAAGUUAUUUCAUCUCUCAGCCUUGAUUUCUUUACCUGUUAAAUGGGGUACUCAUAGCCGUAAAGGAUUUUUUUGUGAAGCCUGAUCGCAAAGCAUCUGGCCCUUUCCAAAUGCUUAAUCAAUAUGUCAUUACUAUUAUUAAUAAACAUUUUCUGAGUGCCUGCUACAUGCCAAA